GCACUUGCUGUGACCCCCACCUGGAGGCUUCUCUGCAGCAGGAGCAGGAGCUGUUACCCUUCUAAUCCCCACAAUGACCCCAGCCUAAUAAUACAAUAAUCCCCAAGUAGAACCAGGGGCCCAAGGCCCCCUCGUCAGCUGGGCUCCCACCUCCAAGCUGACGCCCUCAACCACUCUGCUGGGGUGAGCAAACCCAGGCCCCACAGCUGGCUAGCGGGAUAUCCGUGUCCACGAUUGGCGCCAUGUGUUUUAAGUUGCAGCGUCAAAAACAUGAAGAGAUUGCUUUAGCAAAUAUUUACCCAGUCCUGACUCUGCACAUGGCAUCGUUCUAGGAGCCCAAAGAUGUUAACUUGUUUAAUAAUCAAGCCCUGUGAAGGUCUCACUUUGUCACCCAAGUUGGAGUGCAGAGGCACAAUGACAGCUCACUGCAGCCUCGACUUCCUGGGUUCAAGUGAUCCUCCUGCCCCAGCCUCCCUAGUAGCUGGGACUUCAGGGAGUUUAUAGCAUCUGUGGAUUUUGGUACCCACGGAGGUGCUGGAACCAAUCGUUGAGGAUUCCAAGGACAACUCUAUGAUGCAGGCACACCUGUCCUAGCUGCUCAAGGGUCGUGGGAUGCAGGUGGCACGGUGCACGCCAAGAUGGCUGUGUCCACAGAGGAGCUGGAGGCCACGGUUCAGGAAGUCCUGGGGAGACUGAAGAGCCACCAGUUUUUCCAGUCCACAUGGGACACUGUUGCCUUCAUUGUUUUCCUCACCUUCAUGGGCACCGUGCUGCUCCUGCUGCUGCUGGUCGUCGCCCACUGCUGCUGCUGCAGCUCCCCCGGGCCCCGCAGGGAAAGCCCCAGGAAGGUGAGCCCCUGGAAGGAAAGACCCAAGGGAGUGGAUAACUUGGCCCUGGAACCCUGACCCUGUGUCUCCUGCCCGGUGGCAGUAACAAAGCCUUCUGUCUGCCCAGAGCCUGAGUCUGCAGUGUCUUCCAGUCCCCGUCUGGGUGGGUGACGCGGGACUCGCCGCCCCACUCAGGUGGCCACCUGGCCUCUCCAAGCCUUCAGUCAGCACGACUGUGCCAGGUCAUCCUCAGUCACCUAGCUGGGAGGGGAGCUGGUCUCAGGCCGGGCGCGGUGGCUCACACCUAUAAUCCCAGCACUUUGGGAGGCCGAGGUGGG